AAGAGCAGGAUGAGCCGCGCAAGCUGACAGCCACUGCUGCCGCCCGCGCCCAGGCUCGGUCUCGCUCCCAGCGCUCGGGGCCGCUCCCCGCCUCCCGCCUCCCCCGGCCGCCCGCGGGGCGGCCCGCCCCCUCUGCACCUCCGGGCCCGGAGCUGCCUCCAUCGCUCCUGCAUCCCGGCCGGGGGGAGGAGGAGGCGGAGCAGGAGGCGAGCCGGAGCCGCCGCCGCCAACGCCGCCGCCGCCGCCCGAGCAGGACAGAGCGCGCCGCAGCCCCGCGCGUCCGGCCGCCGCCCGCGCCCAUCCAGCAGCCUCGCCGGAGCCACACCGCGGGACAGACGCGGCCGCGGCGCGUCCCGGCCCGGUCCAGCCCAGCCCAGCCCAGUCCCGGCACCGGGCGGCCCGGCGGCCGGCCCGCCCCCGAGGGCGCCGGGCGCGGCGGGAGGAUGCCGAAGCCGACGCUGCUGCUGCGCGGGGGCUGGGAGCGCGAGCGCAGCCCCGGGGACUCGGAGCUGGGCCGCCAGUUCCGGGACUGGUGCUUGCGCACCUACGGCGACUCGGCCAAAACCAAGACGGUGACACGCAGCAAAUACCAGCGGAUCGCCGAGGUCCUGCAGGGCGGCGGCGGGACUGGCGCGGGCAGCGGCCCCGCAGCCGGCGAGAAAGGCAAGUUCCAGUUCUGGGUGCGCUCCAAGGGCUUCCGCCUGGGCAGCGGCCGGGAACCCAAGAUGGGCCAAGUGGUGUAUGUGCCGGUCAAGACGGGCUCGGGGGCAGAUGGCCUGUCGGAGCCAGAGGGCAUCUCUCUGAAGCGGGUCGCUGUGGUGGAAGAUUUCUUUGACAUCAUCUACUCGAUGCAUGUGGAGAGCUCAGCGGAGCCAGGCAAAGCCCCCAAGCACGCUGGGCAGAAGAAAACCUACCGAGCGAUCGCAGAGACCUAUGCCUUCCUCCCGAGAGAGGCCGUGACCCGGUUCCUGAUGAGCUGUACGGAGUGUCAGAAGAGGAUGCACUUUAACUCCAAUGGCCUGGAACCCAAAGAAAACGAGCCUCCAUCUCCACUGGUCUCUGGGAUUAUUGAUUACAACAUGCCCCUCACCUCCACCUACCUGAAGCAGAUGAAGCUUCGAGUGAUGAAUUCCCAGGAGCAGGAUGAGACUUCUGUGAGCAGCGAGGAUUUUGAUAUGAGCGACUCCACAUGGAUGUCAGCUGACCCGCACCUGGCCUCCAGCCUGAGCCCCAGCCAGGACGAGAGGAUGCGGAGCCCGCAGAACCUCCACAGUCAAGAGGACGAUGACUCCUCCUCUGAGAGUGGCAGCGGCAAUGGCUCCUCCACCCUGAACCCAUCCACGUCGAGCAGCACGCAGGGCGACCCUGCCUUCCCCGAGAUGAAUGGCAACGGCGCCGUGGCCCCCAUGGACUUCACCACGGCCGCCGAGGAUCAGCCCAUCAACCUGUGUGACAAGCUCCCGCCGGCCACGGCACUUGGCACAGCCUCCUACCCCUCGGAUGGCUGCGGUGCCGACGGGCUGCGGAGCCGCGUCAAAUACGGGGUGAAGACCACCCCCGAGUCCCCCCCCUACAGCUCUGGGAGCUACGAUUCCAUCAAGACCGAGGUCAGCGGCUGCCCUGAGGACCUGACAGUGGGCCGGGCCCCGACGGCAGAUGAUGACGACGAUGACCACGAUGACCAUGAGGACAAUGACAAGAUGAACGACUCUGAAGGCAUGGACCCUGAGCGUCUUAAGGCCUUCAACAUGUUUGUGCGUCUCUUUGUGGACGAGAACCUGGACCGCAUGGUGCCCAUCUCCAAGCAGCCCAAGGAGAAGAUCCAGGCCAUCAUCGAGUCCUGCAGCCGGCAGUUCCCUGAGUUCCAGGAGCGGGCCCGCAAGCGCAUCCGCACGUACCUCAAGUCCUGCCGUCGCAUGAAGAAGAACGGCAUGGAGAUGACCAGACCCACGCCACCCCAUCUGACCUCGGCCAUGGCAGAAAACAUCCUGGCAGCUGCCUGUGAGAGCGAGACAAGAAAGGCAGCCAAGCGGAUGCGUCUAGAGAUCUACCAGUCCUCACAGGAUGAGCCCAUAGCCCUGGACAAGCAGCACUCGCGGGACUCCGCAGCCAUCACCCACUCCACCUACUCACUGCCAGCCUCCUCCUACUCCCAGGACCCUGUGUACGCCAACGGCGGCCUCAACUACAGUUACCGCGGGUACGGGGCCUUGAGCAGCAACCUGCAGCCCCCUGCCUCCCUCCAAACAGGAAACCACAGUAAUGGGCCCACGGACCUCAGCAUGAAAGGCGGGGCCUCUACCACCUCCACCACCCCCACGCCCACCCCCUCCAGCACCAGCACCAGCAGGCCCGUGCCCACCGCUCAGCUCAGCCCCACGGAGAUCAGCGCCGUGCGGCAGCUCAUCGCGGGCUACCGGGAGUCUGCUGCCUUCCUGCUGCGCUCUGCAGAUGAACUGGAAAACCUCAUCCUACAGCAGAACUGACCCCACCGGCACCUGGAGCGCACUGCCCUAGGGAAGGAGGCUGUCCCAGCCUGGACCUGGCUUCCUGCCUCACCAGUUGGUACAUUUUGUUUUUGAAAGAGGUGGGAUCCAAAAGAGCUGUUUCUAGCCACACUCCAAGCACCUGAGACUUUGGGCACAAGGACACUUUUUUUUUUUUUUUUUUUUUUUUUUGGAAUCUCACCACACGGGUGCUCUGACCUGCUUGGAAGAGGCCAACGGGGCAGCUCUGGAAGGGUUGGGGGCUCCCCUGACAAGGCGCUGGGGCUGCAGCUCUGUUUAGAAUCACCUUCGUGGACCCUGAUGUUAGAAUCCCACCCCCAGAUAAUUACCUUUCAAGUCUUAGGUGAGCAGAAUUGCAUAUUUAUUGAGAAAAGCAAAGUGGACCCUUUCUUCCUCUCCCCUUAGUAAUUUAUUUUUCUGAAAAUGGAUUCUUUUGUGUUUGUACAGAUUGCUAGUCUGUGUCUGUCUGAUCAGAAGGAUGUAUCCCCAUACCUAACAUUCCAUAUCACUACACUGAUGUGGGCUGGGGCCAGUAGGGGCAGGACAGGUGCCAGGCUGGCUGUUCCUCUGCAUGCCUGGUGCACCCUGUGGCCGCUAGCCCUUGGCCAGGCCAUCCUGUUGCAGAUCCCAGUGCUGCCACAGGGACACCACCAGGCACCUCCCUAGGCAACGCCAAGCAGGAGGACCUCACCCACACCCAUGGCAAAGCAAAACAAAAGAGGCACCCCGACCCCAUUCUACAGAAGCCCCAGUCCAUGGUCACCUGUAUUCUACCUCACACUCCAGCGUGGGCUUUUUCCAGGAUGUGCCCUGAGCCUGUUCUGAACAGCUGUAACCCCAACUCCCCCACACAAUGUGUCUGCCUGGGAGGUAAGUAAGUCCAGACUGGGUGUCCAGGAGCUGGAACCCAGAGAGCGUCCUGUCCCUAACCAGCCACUGCAGCCCUCCAGCUCUGGCCCUCAGCUGCUUGACAGGACGGACUGCUGGGAGAUGGCAGCCGGUUGGCAGGGCCCUUGCCCUCACACCCCGCUGCCCAGGAGCCAGGUCUGAACUUCUGUGCACAGGCCUGGCCCCUCAGACUCACUCCUGCCAAGAGGGGCCACUUCUUCAGGGUGAGCCCCGGCUAUCAGGCAGCCGUGAGCUCCAGGGCGGGCUGCAGCUCCCAUCCCCUUGCGCCAUGUUUGGAGUAAAGGGAUCAGUGGAAGUGGAGGAGCCACUUGGGUUCUCCUAAGACCAGCCCUUCCGGAGGGGCCGGUCCUGGAAGAAACCCAUAAUCCCUGGAGUGUGAAAAAGGGCAAAAAGAAAAAGCUGGCCUGGUUUCCUUCCUCCCUGAUUGAUUGAUUGAUAGGCACUUCCUCUUGCUCAGUGCAAUACCUACCAGUGCUGCUAAACCAGGGACUCGCCCAGACCUCAGCAGGCCCCCAGGGCCUCUCCGUGCAACACUCCGUAGCCAUGACAGCAGCUCUCUGCUGCCCGCCCCUGCCCAGAGCUGGCAGAAGCCCUCUGUUGCCUUUCCUCCCUCAGAGCAGAGAGGCCCCAGGGGAGCCAGGGCCGAGUGGAUCCUAGGAUGGCCACGGAGAGCCACUCGCUCCCAGAACAGGCACCCCUUCCCAAACCAGCUUUUCUGCAGCCAAUUGCCUGUUGCAGCUGUGGCCACUGCCUCCCGGCACUGUGGCAGACUCCCCCCAAGGAGGGAUGGGGGGGGCACCAGUGAGGAUGCCCCAUCCUGCCUCAGGUCCAGAACUCUGAAAGGUAGGGUGCCCACCCCGUGCUUACUUCCGGCCCCUAGAGGUUGGGGGUGGUCGUUAUCUCUCAAGUGGCCUCCAAUACCCCAUCCAGCCACACCACCUCUGCCUUCCAUCUGACCAAUCCCCAGGCCUCUGGUCAGGGCCAGGACACCUGAGACUCACCCUUAGCACAGCACAACCUCCAGUGCCCAAGGCCUCUCCCACACCCCAGCCAUCCACACAUCUGGCCCCACCUGCUCAGUACUACUCAACAUUUGAAUUCGUGUAAAUAUUUAUUUUUGUGUGUGAACAAUACUACAAAGUAAUCAGUAAGAUCUUUUGCAAAAAUGUUACCCCAGGCAAUUAUUUGUGAAAAUCUUAAUGUUAAAACCUGGCAGAGACAAUCGCCACCCUAGAAUUCCUGGUAUCAGUUACUUAACGUGUCACUUCUCCUCCCAGAGGCAGUACCCAAGCUAGACAUGAACCGUUUGCAUUUCUUGGCAGACAGGAGUGAGAAAGACUGGGGAAGGGGCUCCCUCCCCCUACCCACACAAGGAUUAGAUCUAAAGAUCAGCAUAAGCUACAGUUUGAAGUCAUGUUUUUCUGAGUUCAAGCUGUUGGAACUGACCACCCUCCAGCCUGCCUUAGUACUGCGGCAAGAGCGUAGGUUCAAUGUGUUUUCAAGAGAAAGGAAAGAAUAUGUUGUUAAAGUCCAUUGGGCCUCCCAGGCCCCUCCAGGACAAUGGAUUUCAUCAUGUCGACCCCACCUCUUGGGUGGGCUCCUCCUUUCCAGUGAAACUACACCUGAAGCCCUAGAGAUGGCAGAAUCAGGAGCAAGUUUCUGCAUGGAAACAGGAUUCCAUUUAGCUGGCUCAGUCAGGGAACUUGUUUUGCUUUUGUUUUAAAAGAUGCAGCUUCAACCCCUUCCCCCUACUCCCGACUUGGAGGGCACCAAAGAGCUGGUUCUGAUGAACUAAGCUCACUGCUGUCUCACCCUCACCAGAGGGACUGCCUUCUCCCAAAAGGAGCUCCCAAAGCCCUUGUCCCACAGCCAUUUAAAAAUCUUCUGAAGGGCCUCAGGGCACAAAGUGAUCAUUUGGGAUCCUAAGUUAAAAAGGAAAUGCAAGAGUAGGAUACUCCAAUUCCAGAGUCUUUGCAGGAGGCUAAUCCCACAAGAAGGGUAGCAUCAGAGAAGUGGGCAUUGGUCUUAGUGGUGGAUCAUCAGGUAGACAAGUGAUAGUGUGUGUAACCCAUCUGAAAUUCAUUUUACCGUCACCACUCUUACAAAGGACAGUUUAUUCCCAAGGACAGUGCUGACGGGGAGGGGGACAGGCAGGGAGUUAGGAGGGUUUUCGAGGAUUUCAAACAGGUGGAACCCAUCCAUCCCUAUUCCCAAGGGCCACUUACAACUCUAAGGGUGGUUACAGGAUUAACUACCAGUUCAUUUUCAAAAUGCUGCUUUGAACUCAGAGGGUUGAUACUUUUAAUUUGUAAUUUUUUGUAAAACUUUUUACAAAAUAGUAAAGUAUUUCACCAGAAUACCAGUUUCAAUCCGUCCAUGGUCUGAUUUUUAUAUAAUUUAGUGGUGCUUUAGAAACUUUGUUUUUGUUGUUUCUGAGCUAAACAGCUCAAUCCUUUUUCGCCUGUAUCUACCUAAGACCAAUGUGAACCUUUGUAUUUUUGCUCCUAAUUUUGGACUCAGUGAAAGUGUACUGUUUACAUGUACAGAUGCCCCCAGUCCCUGUGUGUUCUGCAAGACUUGCUCUUGAGGAGGAAGAUGCACCUCACUAAGCUCAUCUGCUUAGCAAAGCCACAAACAAAAACCUCUCACUUUUUACCUACGUUUCCACCUAAAAAUACAACAAAAAACCUAUACCACGUAGAACUCAGAUUGGCUGAAAAACACUUUCCACCUGGUAGAUGGCCCAUAUGCCUCAAUUAUGUGGUCCAUUUAGGAGCAGGAGUCAGAAGAGAGACCUCUUAUUGGCUGCUGGUGGGUAACUGCAUGGACAGAGGAAAAGGGAAGGCAGGACUUUGCUGCAGAGCUGUGGGAUGAAUGUAGUUCUUCCCUGGGCAGCCUGGGAGUGGGAAGGUCAGAAUGACUCAUGUUGCCUUCAGGAUCAAGCCAUCCAGGAUUUAGGGACAACCCAAGAGGUCUUUAGUCCUCUGGCAUAAUUUAGACAUGUUUUGGAAGAGCAUGAGUUCCAUAUCUGAGAUGAGAUUUAAGACUUUCAGUGCAGAUAGUACAAGCCAUUUCUUCAGGGUUCCUCUGGGGGCAGCUCCUUCAUGAGGUCCCACCUCCGGGGAGGGGCACAGGGCUCCAGAUAGUAAGCACUUAAGGCAAACAGUGGAUGGCACCAACUUUUAAAGGUGACUCUAUUAAUGGCUUCACCUCUAAAUUAUAUUUUUACAGAUAUGCACCUAUGCAACUUAACGUGGCUCUUCUAAGCAGGUGAGGACUUCCUCCUCAAUGCUCUCUAUAAAAAUUAUUUGUGUUCUAUAUAGUGAGUUUUACCAGUAAAUGUGGCUUAAUAUUUUAAUUCUUAGAAUGUGUCUUCUCUACGUGAUGUGACUAAAUUCUGUUUUGUUUGUGGAAUGACUAGCACAGGCCGACUCCCUCUCUCCCUCACUUAACAAAAGACCAAUGAGCUGUUAAUCGAGCUGUUAUCUCCAUGGUAUUACUUGCUAAAUGCACUGAUUUCAUAAGUAUGUGGAAUCCUUUUCCUUUUGAAUCUGUAUAUCAUAUAUAAGACUGAAUCUACUUAAUAAACACUGAACAACAAACCGAA